AGCCGCCGCUUGGCUUCUUUCACACGGGUUGCUUCGGAGGAAUCCGCCGUGCAAAUCUGUCCGCCCCCUUGGCCACUGAUCCCCCGAAGAGCUUCUGUCGCCGCUCUAGGGUAAAGGAGAGCUGCCCCUGCCCCUGCCCCCGCCUAUCCGAGAAUAGAGACAUUGAAGUUUGGGACAAGAUAUUUAUCUAACUUCUGUGUCAAAAUUAGCGACCUGCUAUGGCAAUGAAGAAAGAAACUGAAUUUGUCAUUUUCACCUGAAGAAAAAUGAUAGACAAAAAUCAAACCUGUGGUGUAGGACAGGAUUCUGUGCCCUAUAUGAUUUGUCUGAUUCACAUACUCGAAGAAUGGUUUGGUGUGGAGCAGUUGGAGGACUAUUUGAAUUUUGCAAACUAUCUCUUGUGGGUUUUUACACCACUAAUACUUUUAAUACUUCCUUACUUUACUAUCUUUCUUCUCUACCUUACUAUUAUUUUCUUACACAUUUAUAAGAGAAAGAAUGUAUUGAAAGAAGCCUACUCUCAUAAUUUAUGGGAUGGUGCAAGGAAAACAGUGGCAACUCUGUGGGAUGGACAUGCAGCCGUUUGGCAUGGUUAUGAAGUUCAUGGAAUGGAAAAAAUACCAGAAGAUGGACCAGCACUUAUAAUUUUUUAUCAUGGAGCUAUUCCUAUAGAUUUUUACUAUUUCAUGGCUAAAAUAUUUAUACACAAAGGCAGAACUUGCCGAGUAGUAGCUGAUCACUUUGUCUUUAAAAUUCCAGGGUUUAGUUUAUUACUGGAUGUGUUUUGUGCUCUACAUGGACCAAGAGAAAAAUGUGUUGAAAUUCUGAGGAGUGGCCACUUGUUAGCUAUCUCACCAGGUGGAGUUCGAGAAGCCCUAAUUAGUGAUGAAACUUAUAACAUCGUAUGGGGUCAUCGCAGAGGCUUUGCUCAGGUUGCAAUUGAUGCAAAAGUGCCCAUUAUUCCUAUGUUUACACAAAAUAUUCGAGAAGGAUUUAGAUCACUUGGAGGAACAAGGUUAUUUAGGUGGCUUUAUGAAAAAUUCCGCUAUCCAUUUGCUCCAAUGUAUGGAGGUUUUCCAGUGAAGUUACGGACCUAUUUAGGCGACCCCAUUCCGUAUGACCCACAGAUAACAGCGGAAGAAUUAGCUGAAAAGACGAAGAAUGCUGUUCAAGCUUUGAUUGAUAAGCACCAAAGAAUACCAGGAAACAUUAUGAGUGCUUUGUUAGAACGUUUUCAUUGAUAACAAAGGGUCAACUAGAAGAUGAUUUAGUACAUUUAUAUUAAAUGUUUGUAUCUAAGGUACUGUCUUCUGAAUUUUGUAGGUCCUAUAAUUAGUAUUUUUUAAAAAAAUCAUGUUAAUAAGCAUCUUUCACAGAAUUCGUUUCUUUAAAAUAGUCAAUUUUGUUUUUGCAAUUGUGUCAAAUACUAACAAAUUACACACCUAGUAAUUCAGAAAAAGAUGUCUUAUUUGUAAAUUCCUAACAAUUUAUGCUAAACAUAUAGAUUCUUAAGUUUAUUAAUAACAGCAGUUUAGGUUAAACAAACAUUCCUGGAUAAUGCGUUAAAUUUCUGUAUCUGUCGCCCUGAGCUGAUUUUGAAAGAUGGUAUAAGCUAGGGGUUAGUAUAGUUGUUUAAGUUAGAAAAAACAUGCUGUUGUCUGCCCCUCAUUCCCUUCAUGACCUUGGGCAAGUCACGUAAUGUUUUUGUGCCUCAACAAUUCACUUUUUAAAAACAUGAUCGUAUGAUGAAUGAUAUUAUUUUGUUAUUUAUAUUUACUGUGAUUGAUAACUGUUGAACCAAAAUAAUAAAAUAAUUAAUUUAAACAAUGUCAAAAUCCUUUAGCAGUUAUGUAUAUAUUUUCUCCAUUGUGUGUUUAAAUUAUGUCAUGUCCAGUUGCCAAGCACAAUGAAAAAGAUGUAUUAUUUUUUAAAUUGAAUAAAAAAUUAGGAAAAAUAAAAUUUCUAAUUAUUAUUUUUAGUAUGAUAUUUUUAACAAGAGUCUAUAGGCAAACAAUAUAGGGUGUGCUGUGCAUUGUCAGCCCUAUACUGUGGUCUUAAUAAUGCCAGCUUAAAAAUCACUGUUGUGCUCUGCAUUUCGUGUGUUAGAAGCUGAUUCUAGGCUGAGGAAAGCAAGAGUUCUCUACUUUUGCUCAAUAUUGAGGCUUACCCAGUUUGACUCUACAGCCAGUGAAGUGGUUUAUUGCUUCAAUAAAAAUAUACUUGAAUGAUGAAUUUAUUUAUGUUUUGUUUUGUUUUUAUUUAGAGAUGGGGUUUUGCCAUGUUGGCCAGGCUGGUCUUGAACUCCUGACCUCAGGUGAUCCACCUGCCUCAGCCUCCCAACUUGCUGGGAUUACAGGUGUGAGCCACCAUGCCCAGCCUGAAUGAUGAAUUUAUGUGAACACAAAGCCCUCUGAAAAAUUAAUGAUUUUCAAUUUGUUGUCUUCUUGAAAACUGAAUUUAAGUAUUAUUUAAACAGAAAAGUGUCAGAAAUCAAAUGCAGUAUCUCCCUCUCCCUUUUUUAAAUGUUGAAUUAGUAGGGUUUUUGUAUAGCUUUUUGUAUUGUGUGUAUUUAUGAUAUGUGAAAUGUACAUAAAAUUAAACAAUGUGAAAAUAAA